AGCAGCGAGUCCUUGCCUCCCGGCGGCUCAGGACGAGGGCAGAUCUCGUUCUGGGGCAAGCCGUUGACACUCGCUCCCUGCCACCGCCCGGGCUCCGUGCCGCCAAGUUUUCAUUUUCCACCUUCUCUGCCUCCAGUCCCCCAGCCCCUGGCCGAGAGAAGGGUCUUACCGGCCGGGAUUGCUGGAAACACCAAGAGGUGGUUUUUGUUUUUUAAAACUUCUGUUUCUUGGGAGGGGGUGUGGCGGGGCAGGAUGAGCAACUCCGUUCCUCUGCUCUGUUUCUGGAGCCUCUGCUAUUGCUUUGCUGCGGGGAGCCCCGUACCUUUUGGUCCAGAGGGACGGCUGGAAGAUAAGCUCCACAAACCCAAAGCUACACAGACUGAGGUCAAACCAUCUGUGAGGUUUAACCUCCGCACCUCCAAGGACCCAGAGCAUGAAGGAUGCUACCUCUCCGUCGGCCACAGCCAGCCCUUAGAAGACUGCAGUUUCAACAUGACAGCUAAAACCUUUUUCAUCAUUCACGGAUGGACGAUGAGCGGUAUCUUUGAAAACUGGCUGCACAAACUCGUGUCAGCCCUGCACACAAGAGAGAAAGACGCCAAUGUAGUUGUGGUUGACUGGCUCCCCCUGGCCCACCAGCUUUACACGGAUGCGGUCAAUAAUACCAGGGUGGUGGGACACAGCAUUGCCAGGAUGCUCGACUGGCUGCAGGAGAAGGACGAUUUUUCUCUCGGGAAUGUCCACUUGAUCGGCUACAGCCUCGGAGCGCACGUGGCCGGGUAUGCAGGCAACUUCGUGAAAGGAACGGUGGGCCGAAUCACAGGUUUGGAUCCUGCCGGGCCCAUGUUUGAAGGGGCCGACAUCCACAAGAGGCUCUCUCCGGACGAUGCAGAUUUUGUGGAUGUCCUCCACACCUACACGCGUUCCUUCGGCUUGAGCAUUGGUAUUCAGAUGCCUGUGGGCCACAUUGACAUCUACCCCAAUGGGGGUGACUUCCAGCCAGGCUGUGGACUCAACGAUGUCUUGGGAUCAAUUGCAUAUGGAACAAUCACAGAGGUGGUAAAAUGUGAGCAUGAGCGAGCCGUCCACCUCUUUGUUGACUCUCUGGUGAAUCAGGACAAGCCGAGUUUUGCCUUCCAGUGCACUGACUCCAAUCGCUUCAAAAAGGGGAUCUGUCUGAGCUGCCGCAAGAACCGUUGUAAUAGCAUUGGCUACAAUGCCAAGAAAAUGAGGAACAAGAGGAACAGCAAAAUGUACCUAAAAACCCGGGCAGGCAUGCCUUUCAGAGUUUACCAUUAUCAGAUGAAAAUCCAUGUCUUCAGUUACAAGAACAUGGGAGAAAUUGAGCCCACCUUUUACGUCACCCUUUAUGGCACUAAUGCAGAUUCCCAGACUCUGCCACUGGAAAUAGUGGAGCGGAUCGAGCAGAAUGCCACCAACACCUUCCUGGUCUACACCGAGGAGGACUUGGGAGACCUCUUGAAGAUCCAGCUCACCUGGGAGGGGGCCUCUCAGUCUUGGUACAACCUGUGGAAGGAGUUUCGCAGCUACCUGUCUCAACCCCGCAACCCCGGACGGGAGCUGAAUAUCAGGCGCAUCCGGGUGAAGUCUGGGGAAACCCAGCGGAAACUGACAUUUUGUACAGAAGACCCUGAGAACACCAGCAUAUCCCCAGGCCGGGAGCUCUGGUUUCGCAAGUGUCGGGAUGGCUGGAGGAUGAAAAACGAAACCAGUCCCACUGUGGAGCUUCCCUGAGGGUGCCCGGGCAAGUCUUGCCAGCAAGGCAGCAAGACUUCCUGCUAUCCAAGCCCAUGGAGGAAAGUUACUGCUGAGGACCCACCCAAUGGAAGGAUUCUUCUCAGCCUUGACCCUGGAGCACUGGGAACAACUGGUCUCCUGUGAUGGCUGGGACUCCUCGCGGGAGGGGACUGCGCUGCUAUAGCUCUUGCUGCCUCUCUUGAAUAGCUCUAACUCCAAACCUCUGUCCACACCUCCAGAGCACCAAGUCCAGAUUUGUGUGUAAGCAGCUGGGUGCCUGGGGCCUCUCGUGCACACUGGAUUGGUUUCUCAGUUGCUGGGCGAGCCUGUACUCUGCCUGACGAGGAACGCUGGCUCCGAAGAGGCCCUGUGUAGAAGGCUGUCAGCUGCUCAGCCUGCUUUGAGCCUCAGUGAGAAGUCCUUCCGACAGGAGCUGACUCAUGUCAGGAUGGCAGGCCUGGUAUCUUGCUCGGGCCCUAGCUGUUGGGGUUCUCAUGGGUUGCACUGACCAUACUGCUUACGUCUUAGCCAUUCCGUCCUGCUCCCCAGCUCACUCUCUGAAGCACACAUCAUUGGCUUUCCUAUUUUUCUGUUCAUUUUUUAAUUGAGCAAAUGUCUAUUGAACACUUAAAAUUAAUUAGAAUGUGGUAAUGGACAUAUUACUGAGCCUCUCCAUUUGGAACCCAGUGGAGUUGGGAUUUCUAGACCCUCUUUCUGUUUGGAUGGUGUAUGUGUAUAUGCAUGGGGAAAGGCACCUGGGGCCUGGGGGAGGCUAUAGGAUAUAAGCAUUAGGGACCCUGAGGCUUUAAGUGGUUUCUAUUUCUUCUUAGUUAUUAUGUGCCACCUUCUUAGUUAUUAUGUGCCACCUCCCCUAUGAGUGACGUGUUUGAUCACUAGCAGAAUAGCAAGCAGAGUAUCAUUCAUGCUGGGGCCAGAAUGAUGGCCGGUUGCCAGAUAUAACUGCUUUGGAGCAAAUCUCUUCUGUUUAGAGAGAUAGAAGUUAUGACAUAUGUAAUACACAUCUGUGUACACAGAAACCGGCACCUGCCAGACAGAGCUGGUUCUAAGAUUUAAUACAGUGCUUUUUUUCCUCUUUGAAAUAUUUUACUUUAAUACCAGUGCCUUUUCUUGUUGAACUUCUUGGAAAAGCCACCAAUUCUAGAUCUUGAUUUGAAUUAAUACACACAAUAUCUGAGACACUUACACUUUUCAAAAGAUUUGUGUAUGCAUUGCCUAAUUAGAGUAGGGGGAGAAGGGCAACUAUUAUUAUCCCUAUUUUACAAAACUGAGGCUUAGUGAGGUUCAGCCACAUGCCUAGACUUAUAUACUAGUUAGUGGUGCAGCCAGGGAGAGGACUCAGAUUUCCUGGAGGCAAAGUCUAUCUCUGAAACUCCAUGAAGACUUUUGCAGCCAGUUCCCACCAAUAUGCCCCAGACGUGAGACAAACAAGGACUUUUUUUUUUAUAUAGAGCCAUCCAUAAAAUCCUAAGCCCUUUUAUUAAUGUAUAACCAGGAGAACAUCUGUGCCAACGGUUGGACUUUUUAUGGCUGAGAUUCGGGAGGAAGUGUGACACCAAGCAGGAGAGGAAGAAUGAUUUUCUUUGUACUUAGGUUUUCUAAGGACAUUGUUUUAAUCUGUAUCGUGCCAAAGUUGUAUCACUGUUAAACUUCUGAAGACAUAACCAGUUGAGUCUUAUUUCAAGAUAUGUUCUCAAGCCAAUUGUGUGCUUCUCUUGUUUCUGUGAUUGCUUUCUAGCCAAAGCGAAGCUUGUACAGGUUGAGUAUCCCUUAUCCAAAAUGCUUGGAACCAGAAGUGUUUCAAAUUUUAGAUUAUUUUCAGAUUUUGGAAUGUUUGCAUAUACAUAAUGAGAUAUUUUGGGAAUAGGACCCGAGCCUAAACACAAAAUUCAUUGAUGUGUCAGUUACACCUUAUCCACAUAGCCUGAGGGUAAUUUUAUACGAUAUUUUAAAUAGUUGUGUACAUGAAGCAUGGUUUGUGGUAACUUAUGUGAGGGGUUUUCCCAUUUUUUGUCUUGUUGGUGCUCAAAAAGUUUUGGAUUUUGGAGCAUUUCGGAUUUUGGAUUUUUGGAUUAGGGUUGCUCAACCCAUAUUAUUGGCUGUACAUCCUGGUCACUUCUGACUUCUGUUUUUACUAAUGGAAGCUUUGCAAAUUGAAUUCUCAGUGAGUUGUAUAUUUAUACACCUGGCUUGAAGCCUUAAUUGUAUAUAAUGAUGCUUUUUAAAAAAUGCUAUUUGGAAGACUAUUUAUUUCUCGUGUAUAUAAUGUAUAUAAAAAAAUAUGGUUAGUGUUUACCUAAGGUUAACCAAUUUCAAGAUUAAAAUUUUUAAAUAGUAAAAUAAUAAAAAAUUAUAAAGUUCUUAAUGGUCUGACAACUCAAUUUUUUUUUUUUUUUUUUUUUUUUUUGAGACAGAGCCUCUCUCUGUCACCCAGGCUGGAGUGCAGUGGCAAUCUUGGCUCACUACAACCUCUGCCUCCUGGGCUCAGGUGGUCCUCCCACCUCAGCCUUCUGAGUAGCUGGGAUUACAGAGAUGCGUCACCAUGUCUGGCUAAUUUUUGUAUUUUUAGUAGAGAUGGGGUUUCGCCAUGUUGGCCAGGCUGGUCAGGCUGGGUUCGAACUCCUGGCCUCAAGUGAUCCGCCUGCCUCAGCCUCUGAAAGUUCUGAGAUUAUAGGUGUGAGCCACCGUGCCUGGCCAAUUCUUAAAGUUUGAAAGAAUAUAGCUGCCCCAACCUAGAGUCUGACAAAAAGUUACUCUAAUAUAAGGCAUAUUCUUUAUUUGACACUCAUCGUUAGCAGAAGUGGACAGCAAUUCACUAAAGAACCAGAACAAGAACAUCAUUUCACUGAAGACGAGAAGAAAAAUUAUUUCAAUUGUAGCAGCUUGAAGGCCUGAAGGUGGAUGUUAGGAAGAACAGGGAGCAUGGCUGGACACUGGGGAGCAUUAGUGAGAUUAUUAGGUUUGGUUGAAUUGGAACUAGAUAUCAGUGACUUAGACCAGAGGGAAGCUGAUUUCUCUAUUGGUUAAAGUCCCAGCUGGUAGUAAGGUUCUAUUCUACAGGCCAAGAGGGCUGCAGGUUCUUAGUUUUUCACUGUGCCAUUCAUGGGGUAUUCCUCGCAUCCCCACAGCCCAGGGGUCCCCUACCAGCCAAUGGAAAGCCAGAAAAGGGAAGGGAUGAACAGUCUCCUCUUAAAGACAUGACUGAGAAGUUGCUUACAUUCUAUUGGCCAGAAAUAAAUCCAUGGUCACAUGACAGGCUGGGAAAUACAGUCUUUAUUUAGGGUGCCCAUGGGCCCUGCUGAAGAUCCAAUUACUAUUUAUUUAAAAUUGACAUAUAAUAAUUGUACAUAUUUGUGGGGAAAAUAGUGAUGUUUCGAUACAUACAAGGUAUAGUGAUCAUGUUGGAAUAAUUAGCAUACCCAUCCUUUCAAACAUGUAUCAUUUCUUUGUGUUGGGAACAUUCAAUAUCCUCCUUCUAGUUACUUGAAACCAUAUUUUAUUAACUCUAGUUUUACCCUUCAGUGGUAUAGGACACUAGAAUUUAUUCCUCCUGUCUAGCUGUAAUCUUGUUUGUUUCGUUUGGUGUUUUUUGUUUUUUUGUUUUUUUUUGAGAUGGAGUCUUGCUCUGUAGCCCAGGCUGGAGUGCAGGGGCAUGAUCUUGGCCCACUGCAACCUCCGCCUCCUGGGUUCAAGUGAUUCUCCUGCCUCAGCCUCCCAAGUAGCUGGGAUUACAGGCAUGCACCACCACACCCAGCUAAUUUUUGUAUUUUUAGUAGAGACAAGGUUUCACCAUGUUGGCCAGGCUGGUCUUGAACUCCUGACCUCAAGUGAUCCACCUACCUCAGCCUUCCAAACUGUCGGGAUUACCGGUGUGAGCCACCGGGCCCAGCCACUAGCUGUAAUUUUGUAUCUUUUAACAAUUCCGUCCCUAUUUCCCCUUUCCCCCUACCAAUUACUAUUUAUUAAAAGGGAAAUUGGAUCUUGCCAUCCGUUUAUCAGGAAUUAGUUUUUUCUCUGCUAAAGCCAGCGAGAUAGACCAGAGUACCCUUUAAAUGAUUAAAUCCUGUAGUCAAUUUUUAGUAAUCUUAAAUUGAUCUAUGACUAUGAAGUAUAAUGCAUUACAUCAGUUUGACUUUAUUUCUGGUCUUAAGUGUGAAAACAUUUCUAAAUGACAAGGAAGCUCUUUAUAAAGGGCUUUAGUGAUGGUGGAAACUCCACUGUCCAUCUCUACCAGGACAUUCUGAAACCAGGCUUGAUAAUGGCUGUAGGGAGUUGGGUUAGACAAUAAGAGAUAAGUUCUUAACUUGGUUCAGAUGUCAGAGGAAAGCAGAAAAUGGUGUCUCUGGCAUAGUAAAGAAAAUUGUUGAAAUUUCCCAAAGGAAGAGUCAUAGCCUGGAUGACUGCAAGUGCCUUCUUUGGCUUGGGGGUUCAGUUACUAGUUAGAGUCAGGGGAACUUCCACAGGACUUCCUUUGACUCUCCAAACAAGCUGAAGCCCCAGACCCCUUGGAAGGAUGGAUACAAAGUAGGUACUAGAACAGUCUUUGUCAUCAAAUAUGGUAUUUCUCAGGUGUCACCUCUGUGUUCAGAGCUACCCUGAGCCCUCUGCCAUGUAAGCUCUCUGAUGGCACAGAUUUUUAUCUGGCUUGUUUUCUGCCGUUAUCUUAGAAGCUAGAAUAGUGUCUGGAACAUCAUGGGUAUUCAAUGAAUAUUUAAAUAAAUAGAUGAAAUUAGAUAUAAGAAACUAGGUGCUUAAACAGGCAGGAGGUAAUCUGGGAAAAGAGCAGUUAGUUUGGAAUCAGAAUUCUUGGUGUGUCAUCCAGCAUUAUGUGAGUUUUAGGCUAAAUACAGCCUUUCUGAGUCUCUAUCUGCUCAUUUAAGAAACAGAGACAAUACUGCUCAGGGUUGUUGUGAAUGUUAAAGGUACAUGGUAAAAAAGAAAGUAUUUGUGUUUUGUAAACAUUUGAAUUGAUAAGAGGACAGUGUGAGACAAAAAUAAAAUCCUGGGUGGGCACGGUGGCUCACCCCUGUAAUCUCAGCACUUUGGGAGGCUGAGAUGGGAGGAUCACGAGGUCAGGAGUGCGAGACCAGCCUGGCCAAUAUGGUGAAACCACGUCUCUGCUAAAAAUACAAAAAUUAGCUGGGCGUGGUGGCACGUGCCUGUAGUCCCAGCUACGCCGGAGGCUGAGGCAGAAGAAUCGCUCGAACCUGGGAGAUGGAGUUUGCAGUGAGCUGAGAUCACGCCACUGCACUCCAGCCUAGGCAACUGAGUGAGACUCCAUCUCAAAAUAAAAUAAAAUAGAAUAGAAUAAAAUAAAAUCCUUUCCACAUAUAUGCGGAAAUUUUAUGUAUGAUAAAAGGGGCCUAUUAGUCUUUGGGAAAGGAAUGGAUGGAUGAUGAGAAAGUAGGCUCAUUUGACAAAGAGAAACAAAAUUAGAUUCCUAUUUUAACACGCAACAAAGAUGAAUUCCAAAAUACCUAUUGGGUACUAUGCUUAUUACCUGAGUGACGAAAUAAUCUGUACAGCAAACUCCUGUGACACACCAUUUAACUACAUAACAAACCUGCAUACGUACCCCUGAAACUAAAGUAGAAGUUAAAACCAUCAACCCCCCCAAAACAAAAAUGAAUUCCAUCUGAAUAAAAGGUAUAAAUGUGAAAGUCAUCAUGCUAAUAGAUAUUAUGAAAUAUAAAUUCAAAACCUGUAUAAAAACUGAAAAAAUGUAAAACGUCACAAUUAGAAUAAGAAAAUUUAAAUAGAACAAUGAAUAUUAAAUAAACUAAAAUGCUAAUAAAAUGUACUCCUUAGGGCCAGGUGCGGUGGCUCACACCUGUAAUCCCAGCACUUUGGGAGGCCGAGGUGGGUGGAUCACCUGAGGUCAGGAGUUUGAGACCAGCCUGGCCAAUGUGGUGAAACCCUGUCUCUACUAAAAAUACAAAAAGUUAGCCAGGUGUGAUGGUGGGCACCUGUAAUCCCAGCUACUUGGGAGGCUGAGGUAGGAAAAUCACUUGAACCCAGAAGGCAGAAGUUGCAGUGAGCCUAGAUCACGGCACUACACUCCAGCCUGGGCAACAAGAGCAAAUCUCUAUCUCAAAAAAAAAAAAAAAAAAAAAAAGGCCACAGAAAUGUCCAUCCAGCAGGUGGACAAUUACCCUUUUGUCAGCCGUUCCUCUGUUGCUGACCAUUAGAUCCACAUUUCUUUUCUGUCCGCCCUGGUCCCCUGGUGCCCCCUUUCCUGGCCCCUGUGACAUAUUGUCAUGUAGCUCCAAGUAUUUCCCCCCCUCAUAUCCCUCAAGUGCUCCAUUUUCCAAAUGCAUUUGACUUCCUACUCUCUUAGCCCCAGCUCUCUGGUAUUCUGUGUAGCUGACUUCCACAAGGGAUCUGUUGGGAGCUUGUAACUGAACUGAAGUCAUGCACAUUGUCAAUGGCUAGUAGACCUUUACCUGGUCCAGAGUUGUCUGCAUUGUUUAAAGAAGACGUUUGUUAAUCCAAAUUAAUCUUUGAUUUGCAUGGAGGCAGUAGGUCAAAUCAAAAGGAAAUUUUCCUCUCCCUAGCAAGCAAACUCAGAAACAAACAAACAAACGAAAACCAAGAAACAAAAGGAAAGGUUCCUGUUGGGAUAGAGAAACAGUGGAGCAGGGCAGCCACCUUACACAUAGGCUAGAUCUGCUUGGGAAUCUUUCUUCUAAUCGAGGCCCCUAAAAUAUUCCUGAUUUUCACAGUUGAUUUCAUUUCUUCCCUCCUGAACUUACAGAGCCUUUCAGUAAACACCAGUAUUUGUCCCUCCCCGUGUAUGCCCAGUGGUUUCCAUGGCAGCAACGGUUGCCAUAGAGAGGUGAAGAGAGGUGUCGGUGCCCUCUUUUGUAACUGUGGGUUAUCUAUAGAUUGGGGGUGGCCUCUCCUAAAAAAGACUAAUAUGUAAAUAAAAGGAAUAAGAAUCAAACAAAUAUAAAUCAGGGCUCAAGUCAUUUGUUUUCCUAAACCUUUGUGGUUAUCCAUACCAUUUAACCUUGACUUUCCUUAAAUCAUACCGGUGCGUGUGUGUGUGCAGAGGGAAAGGGCUGCAAGAAGACUCUGGAAGCUAGGACAGGUCUCAGCAGGUGAGGGCUCAGGCCCAGAGGCCAGCUGGGGCAGCAGGGAGCAGAGUUAUCUGGGCCAUUUGCUAAUUAUCUCAGCCCAGACGAGUCUGCACGCUAUGUGGUUUAAUACCUUCACCAGAGGCAAAUGGUUUUGGACUCACAAGAAUUGCUCAUGGCCAGAGGCAAUGGACAGAUGCCAUAUGAGAAAGGGCUGAGGCCAGGAACAGAGGCAGGGUUAUCUCACUGGAAUGGAGAAGCUAAAAUGACAUUAUCUUUACUUCUGCCCUGGUUAUUAUCCCAAGGCAACUUCAGUGGGCUUGUUUUGAAGUCAAAGCCUCAACUAUUUAUUGUGAGGGAGAUAAUUCAUUUUCAUUUUCCUGCCAGAGAUGUCAGUCUUACUAUUCAUCCUGUAUCCUCUAUUAGAUACACAGAGCUUCUUCCUUCUGCUUAGGCUGCCCCAAAUUCCAUAUAGGAUUCUUUUUGAAGAAUAUAUAUCAUCCAAAAAGAGGUCCUAGGAAAUGUGGCUUCACAACCCUGGGGUUUGUUUCCCUGGCUGCUGUCUCUCUCUCUCUCUUUUUUAAUUUUUUUUGGAGACACGGUAUCACUGUGUGGCCCAGGCUGGAGUGUGGUGGCGCCAUCACUGCUCACUGCAGCCUCGACCUCCUGGGCUCAAGCAGUCCUCCCACUUCAGCCUCCCAAAUAGCUGGGACUACAGGUGUACUCCACUAUGCCUGGCUACAUUUUGAAUUUUUUGUAGAGAUGGGGUUUUGCCAUGUUGCUCAGGUUGGUCUCAAACUCCUGGGCUCAAGCAAUCCACCCAACUUGGCCUCCCAAAGUGCUGGGAUUAGAGGCAUGAGCCAUCAGGCCUGGCCAUGCUGCCUCUCUCUCCUUCAAGGUAGACUUCCUCUUUCCUUCCCCUUCUCCCUGCUUCUUUCUCCUUCUCCUCUCCUUCUCCUCUUCUCCUUCUUCUUCUCACAGCUUUUUAUUGACUUAUAACAGGCACACAAUAAACUGCACACAGGUAAAUCAUAUAAUUUGACAUUUUGGUACAGGAAAUCAUCAUGAAACUGAAAGCAUUACCACAUCGAGAUUGUGAACAUACCACCACCAGAAGUUUUCUUGUGCCCCUUUGUAAUUCUUCCCACUGCCCUCUCCCCAGGUUGUCCCUGAUCUGCUUUUUGUCCUUGUAGAUUAGUUGCAUUUUCUAGAAUUUUGUAUAAGUGGAGUGUAUCUACAGUAUGUUCUCUUUUGUGUCUGCCUUCUUGUACUCAGCAUAAUUAUUUUGAGAUUCAUCCACGUCUUUGCAUGGAUCAGUCAUCUGUUCCAUUUUAUUGCUAAGCAGUAUUCCACUGUAUAGAUAAAUAACAUUUUGUUUAUCCGUUUACUUGUUGAUGAACUUUAAGUUGUUUCCAGUUUUGAGUUAUUAGAGUAAUGCUACUAUGAACAUUUGCAUAUGAAUCCUUGUAUGGACAUGAACUUUCAUUUCUUUUGGGAGUAGGAUAGCUGGAUCAUAUGGAAUGUAUAUGUUUAACUUUUAAAUAAACUGCCAAACUGUUUUCCAAA